CCUAACGUGCUGGGAUUACAGGCAUGAGUCACUACGCCUGGCUCAAAAUUUUUAAAAGGCAUAAAAAGCAGUAUACAUUUAGGUAGAUUCUUUAUUAAUUUCUUUGGUCAUUUCAUAAGUAUUGUCCAUCUACUGUAUGUCAGGCACUGUGCCAGACAGAGAGUCAAGACAGAGCCACAGCCCCUGGUCUCAAGAAAUUUAGAGAAUGAUAAAAUGAACCAGUGGUUAUAACAUUGUAUGGUAAGUGUUGUACAGUUAAGAAGUAUAAUAAGUGCAAGAGGCUGAGGUAGGCUUUCCGGAGGAGGUGACAUCUAGAGCUGUGUGUACCAAGAAUGACCUAGAGAUAUGAGAGAGCAUGGAAUUUGGGGAAACGUAAGUAUGCAUGACUGGAACAUAUGGUGCUAAGUAAAGAACUAAGAAAUGAAGUUGUAGGUGGCAGAAAGAAACAGGACUCAGAUCAUGAAGACUGCUGUAUAUCAUGAUAAAGAGUUUGGAUUUUUUCCCUCCUAAAGGUUAUUUUAUCAAUUAUCUUUUGCUGGUUAAUAAGCCAAUCUAAAACUUAGUGGAUUAAAACAGCAACUAUUUAUUUAGCUCAUAAAUCUGUGUCUUGGCAAUUGAGACUGGUGUCAGUUGGGAGAUUUCCCCAGUCCUGGCUGAACUCACUCAUGUAUAUGUGGUUGGGUACUGGCCACAGGCAACUUAGCUUCUGAGGAACAGGAUGUUAGAUGGAAUGGCAGGAGAGAUUUGGCCACGUUUCUCUUAUCAUUCAUCAGGGUAGCCUGGGUUUGUUCACAUGGCAACUGGCAGGCUUUUAAGACUGAGAGCGGAAGUAAGCAAGGCCUUUUGAAAUCUCACCUUGGAACUAGCGCAGAGUUGCUCCUGCACAUUCUAUUGGCCAAAAGAAGUCUUACAGGCAGCCCAGAUCCAGGCGGUGGAGAAAUAGACCACAUUUCUUGAUUGAAGAAGCUGCAAAAUCACAUUGCAAAGCAGUGUAGAUACAGGGUAUGUUGAAAGUUGUGGCCAUUUUUGCAAUGUCACAGUCAUAGAGAAAAUUGAAGAAUUUUAAGCAGGGAAUUGAUAUAAUUGGAUUGGACUUAUAGAAACAUGAUUUUUACAGAGGUGUGGAAAAUGGAUAAAUGAGGACAAAUUUGGAGGGAAAGAGAGGUUAGAAGGAUAAUUCAUUAAUUCAAUUGAGAAAUAUUGUCAGACUGAUCUAUGGCUAGUGUUAGCGAAAAAAGAGAAGAUGAAGUAAUUUUGAAUGAUAAAGGAGGUAGAGGCUUGAUGAAUAUUCAGUUCUGGGAAAUAAGGGACCCAGAGAAGUAAAGUAUGGCUCCAAUAUUCUGACUUUGUAAACUCAGAAAUCAUUAAGUUUUUCAAAGAGGUAGACAAUAUAGGAUCAGUAGCAGGUUUGGGUUGGAAGAUGGUGAUUUAAGUUUUGGGCAUGUUGAGUUUUAUAUGGCUGUGAGAACCUCAAAUGGAUGUGUCUACUGGGAGACACAUUUGUCUGGAUUUAGGGAGAGAGGUCUGAGCUUUGGAAGUCCUUCACAUAGAGGUAGCAGGUGAUGCCGUGGGAAUAUAUGAUAUCACUCACGGAGAUAACUUAGUAUGAGAAAGACGGAUAAGGAUGGAACUCUGGGAAAUGUUACAUUUUAAAAGAGGUGGAUGGAGGAAACGGAGCUCAUCAAAGAGUGUAAGAAGCAGCAGCAAGAAAGUUUUCUUUCAAAAAUAUUCUCAGCUUCUUGAAAAAAAGACUACAAAAGAGCUGGUUCAUACAACAUUGGAGUGUGUGAAAAAAAAUAUGCCCGUGGAAGAGACAGCCUGGAGCUGUUGCCCAAAGAAUUGGAAGUCAUUUAGUUCCAACUGCUACUUUAUUUCUACUGAAUCAGCAUCUUGGCAAGACAGUGAGAAGGACUGUGCUAGAAUGGAGGCUCACCUGCUGGUGAUAAACACUCAAGAAGAGCAGGAUUUCAUCUUCCAGAAUCUGCAAGAAGAAUCUGCUUAUUUUGUGGGGCUCUCAGAUCCAGAAGGUCAGCGACAUUGGCAAUGGGUUGAUCAGACACCAUACAAUGAAAGUUCCACAUUCUGGCAUCCACGUGAGCCCAGUGAUCCCAAUGAGCGCUGCGUUGUGCUAAAUUUUCGUAAAUCACCCAAAAGAUGGGGCUGGAAUGAUGUUAAUUGUCUUGGUCCUCAAAGGUCAGUUUGUGAGAUGAUGAAGAUCCACUUAUGAACUGAACAUUCUCCAUGAACAGGUGGUUGGAUUGGUAUCUGUCAUUGUAGGGAUAGAUAAUAAGCUCUUCUUAUUCAUGUGUAAGGGAGGUCCAUAGAAUUUAGGUGGUCUGUCAACUAUUCUACUUAUGAGAGAAUUGGUCUGUACAUUGACUGAUUCACUUUUUCAUAAAGUGAGCAUUUAUUGAGCAUUUUUUCAUGUGCCAGAGCCUGUACUGGAGGCCCCCAUUGUGCACACAUGGAGAGAACAUGAGUCUCUCUUAAUUUUUAUCUGGUUGCUAAAGAAUUAUUUACCAAUAAAAUUAUAUGAUGUGGUGUCUC